UAAAAUGAUUAGGUACCUAGUAUCAACCUAGCCAUCCAACCUUAUAUUAAUAACUAGGAAAAUAAAGGGUUGGAGCCUCUGUGUUUCUUUGUUGAAAAAUCUGCUACUAUUAUUAGAUCUGUGAAAACAAUUGAAAAUUCGGUUAUUAUCACCUUAAAAGUACAAAACCUAUAGAUUUUGAAAAUGUAAUUAUUUUUCUGUAGGCAUAGUUAAAAAGAUUUUGUAAAUGUUAUAAAUCAGUUUCUUUAUAAGCGGUUUAUUUAGAUAAAUUUUGUUAUACUGACAUGAUUCACUAAUUUUCUAAAUAUAAAUGGUUCAGCUCUUAGUUAUUUUUAAACUAAUGACCUGUGUUAUACUUCCUAUUUUUAAUGGGCUUUUAUGAUGUUUUAGGUUUUUUUGAAUCCCGUGUCCUUCAAGUGCUUUCUAACUUUGAGAGGAAGAAAUUGACCACCUGGACUAUGGAACUUUGGUUGAAUCUGGCGAUGUGGAACCCAUGGAUAUGGAGGGCUGACUAUAUACACCAUGUUUUUUCCUGGCACAUCACUCAACUACUAUUAGCUGGCGAGUCAACUCACGUUGUUGGAAUGACUAGGGACAACUAGACUUCAAGUGAUCUUUCAUCCCAGGAAUAUAAAUAGUUUCUGGAAAGGACACUGACAACUUCAAAGCAAAAUGAAGUUCUUUCUGUUGCUUUUCACCAUUGGGUUCUGCUGGGCUCAGUAUUCCCCAAAUACACAACAAGGACGGACAUCUAUUGUUCAUCUGUUUGAAUGGCGAUGGGUUGAUAUUGCUCUUGAAUGUGAGCGAUAUUUAGCUCCCAAGGGAUUUGGAGGGGUUCAGGUCUCUCCACCAAAUGAAAAUGUUGCAAUUCACAACCCUUUCAGACCUUGGUGGGAAAGAUACCAACCAGUUAGCUAUAAAUUAUGCACAAGAUCUGGAAAUGAAGAUGAAUUUAGAAACAUGGUGACUAGAUGUAACAAUGUUGGGGUUCGUAUUUAUGUGGAUGCUGUAAUUAAUCAUAUGUCUGGUAAUGCUGUGAGUGCAGGAACAAGCAGUACCUGUGGAAGUUACUUCAACCCUGGAAGUAGGGACUUUCCAGCAGUCCCAUAUUCUGGAUGGGAUUUUAAUGAUGGUAAAUGUAAAACUGGAAGUGGAGAUAUCGAGAACUACAAUGAUGCUACUCAGGUCAGAGAUUGUCGUCUGGUUGGUCUUCUUGAUCUUGCACUGGAGAAAGAUUAUGUGCGUUCCAAGAUUGCCGAAUAUAUGAAUCAUCUCAUUGACAUUGGUGUUGCAGGGUUCAGACUUGAUGCUUCCAAGCACAUGUGGCCUGGAGACAUAAAGGCAAUUUUGGACAAACUGCAUAAUCUAAACAGUAACUGGUUCCCUGCAGGAAGUAAACCUUUCAUUUACCAGGAGGUAAUUGAUCUGGGUGGUGAGCCAAUUAAAAGCAGUGACUACUUUGGAAAUGGCCGGGUGACAGAAUUCAAGUAUGGUGCAAAACUCGGCACAGUUAUUCGCAAGUGGAAUGGAGAGAAGAUGUCUUACCUAAAGAACUGGGGAGAAGGUUGGGGUUUCAUGCCUUCUGACAGAGCACUUGUCUUUGUGGAUAACCAUGACAAUCAACGAGGACAUGGGGCUGGAGGAGCCUCUAUUCUUACCUUCUGGGAUGCUAGGCUGUAUAAAAUGGCAGUUGGAUUUAUGCUUGCUCAUCCUUAUGGUUUUACACGAGUAAUGUCAAGCUACCGUUGGCCAAGACAGUUUCAAAAUGGAAACGAUGUUAAUGAUUGGGUUGGGCCACCAAAUAAUAAUGGAGUAAUUAAAGAAGUUACUAUUAAUCCAGACACUACUUGUGGCAAUGACUGGGUCUGUGAACAUCGAUGGCGCCAAAUAAGGAACAUGGUUAAUUUCCGCAAUGUAGUGGAUGGCCAGCCUUUUACAAACUGGUAUGAUAAUGGGAGCAACCAAGUGGCUUUUGGGAGAGGAAACAGAGGAUUCAUUGUUUUCAACAAUGAUGACUGGACAUUUUCUUUAACUUUGCAAACUGGUCUUCCUGCUGGCACAUACUGUGAUGUCAUUUCUGGAGAUAAAAUUAAUGGCAAUUGCACAGGCAUUAAAAUCUACGUUUCUGACGAUGGCAAAGCUCAUUUUUCUAUUAGUAACUCUGCUGAGGAUCCAUUUAUUGCAAUUCAUGCUGAAUCUAAAUUAUAAAAUUUAAAAUUAAAUGCAUAUCCUCAAAACAAUA